GGCUGCCGGCUCUCAGAUCGGGAUGAUAGUCAAUUCCUUCACUAACGUCACUGUGGCCAUGAUCAUUGCCUUCUCCUUUAGCUGGAAGCUGAGCCUGGUCAUCUUGUGCUUCUUCCCCUUCUUGGCUUUAUCAGGAGCCACACAGACCAGGAUGUUGACAGGAUUUGCCUCUCGAGAUAAGCAGGCCCUGGAGAUGGUGGGACAGAUUACAAAUGAAGCCCUCAGUAACAUCCGCACUGUUGCUGGAAUUGGAAAGGAGAGGCGGUUCAUUGAAGCACUUGAGACUGAGCUGGAGAAGCCCUUCAAGACAGCCAUUCAGAAAGCCAAUAUUUACGGAUUCUGCUUUGCCUUUGCCCAGUGCAUCAUGUUUAUUGCGAAUUCUGCUUCCUACAGAUAUGGAGGUUACUUAAUCUCCAAUGAGGGGCUCCAUUUCAGCUAUGUGUUCAGGGUGAUCUCUGCAGUUGUACUGAGUGCAACAGCUCUUGGAAGAGCCUUCUCUUACACCCCAAGUUAUGCAAAAGCUAAAAUAUCAGCUGCACGCUUUUUUCAACUGCUGGACCGACAACCCCCAAUCAGUGUAUACAAUACUGCAGGUGAAAAAUGGGACAACUUCCAGGGGAAGAUUGAUUUUGUUGAUUGUAAAUUUACAUAUCCUUCUCGACCUGACUCGCAAGUUCUGAAUGGUCUCUCAGUGUCGAUUAGUCCAGGGCAGACACUGGCGUUUGUUGGGAGCAGUGGAUGUGGCAAAAGCACUAGCAUUCAGCUGUUGGAACGUUUCUAUGAUCCUGAUCAAGGGAAGGUGAUGAUAGAUGGUCAUGACAGCAAAAAAGUAAAUGUCCAGUUCCUCCGCUCAAACAUUGGAAUUGUUUCCCAGGAACCAGUGUUGUUUGCCUGUAGCAUAAUGGACAAUAUCAAGUAUGGAGACAACACCAAAGAAAUUCCCAUGGAAAGAGUCAUAGCAGCUGCAAAACAGGCUCAGCUGCAUGAUUUUGUCAUGUCACUCCCAGAGAAAUAUGAAACUAACGUUGGGUCCCAGGGGUCUCAACUCUCUAGAGGGGAGAAACAACGCAUUGCUAUUGCUCGGGCCAUUGUACGAGAUCCUAAAAUCUUGCUACUAGAUGAAGCCACUUCUGCCUUAGACACAGAAAGUGAAAAGACGGUGCAGGUUGCUCUAGACAAAGCCAGAGAGGGUCGGACCUGCAUUGUCAUUGCCCAUCGCUUGUCCACCAUCCAGAACGCGGAUAUCAUUGCUGUCAUGGCACAGGGGGUGGUGAUUGAAAAGGGGACCCAUGAAGAACUGAUGGCCCAAAAAGGAGCCUACUACAAACUAGUCACCACUGGAUCCCCCAUCAGUUGACCCAAUGCAAGAAUCUCAGACACACAUGACGCACCAGUUACAGGGGUUGUUUUUAAAGAAAAAAACAAUCCCAGCAGGAGGGAUUGCUGGGAUUGUUUUUUCUUUAAAGAAGAAUGUUAAUAUUUUACUUUUACAGUCAUUUUCCUACAUCGGAAUCCAAGCUAAUUUCUAAUGGCCUUCCAUAAUAAUUCUGCUUUAGAUGUGUAUACAGAAAAUGAAAGAAACUAGGGUCCAUAUGAGGGAAAACCCAAUGUCAAGUGGCAGCUCAGCCACCACUCAGUGCUUCUCUGUGCAGGAGCCAGUCCUGAUUAAUAUGUGGGAAUUAGUGAGACAUCAGGGAGUAAGUGACACUUUGAACUCCUCAAGGGCAGAGAACUGUCUUUCAUUUUUGAACCCUCGGUGUACACAGAGGCGGGUCUAUAACAGGCAAUCAACAAACGUUUCUUGAGCUAGACCAAGGUCAGAUUUGAAAAGAACAGAAGGACUGAAGACCAGCUGUGUUUCUUAACUAAAUUUGUCUUUCAAGUGAAACCAGCUUCCUUCAUCUCUAAGGCUAAGGAUAGGGAAAGGGUGGAUGCUCUCAGGCUGAGGGAGGCAGAAAGGGAAAGUAUUAGCAUGAGCUUUCCAGUUAGGGCUGUUGAUUUAUGCUUUAACUUCAGAGUGAGUGUAGGGGUGGUGAUGCUACCAUUACUGUGAGGACCUACCAGUGUGGCUGGAGCAGGGACUCUCUCCCAGGCCUUUUACUCCUCAGCACCUCCCUGCAUACUGAUUGUUGUUUUUAGUUUCUGUGAAAUUAUAUUCAUGAAAUGAAAAUAGCGCAUUUUACUUUGCUGUAGUUUCAUAAGGUUUUAUACAAAAAAGCAAGUAAAUAUGGCAGAAAAGCACUCAUUUGCCCCUGCUCCCUCAAAACACCACAGAAUGACAUAGAACUAAAGGCGGCAGGAAUCUACAAGAAUGAAGAAAACACAGUGAUGCCACCUGCAAAAUCUUGGGAGCCAGAAAGCAAAUGGACAAUUGAUAAUAGAGUUACAAGAUGAGAGAAAACAAAAAUGUAACCUGUUAGUUGGGGGAGCCUAGAAACAUCCUGUUUUGUACCACAGACCCCUAGAAAGUUUCAAGAUGUAAAAACACUGGAUCCUUCUGGAAGGAGGAGACAAGGGGACAGAGGGACUGAAGACAGAAGAAUGGACCAAAAGCCUGUAUGGAAACAGAAUUGCAGAGCCCCGCCUGCAGCAGGAUGGCUGCCUUUCCCCAGUUCCAGCGAGAAACUGCAUACUCCCUCUCUGAGGAGGCUCACAGGGAGGUUUGCACUUAGAGACACAAGAUGAAGUUGAAGGGGCAGCUAACAUACAAGAGACAGGGGGAUUGAAUGUAAAGCUGUGUAUGAACAGAAGAACUCCCAGCCCCUCUCUUCUGGCAGGAGAUUGAAGAAUGAUUUUCUGGGGAAAUUGGCCAAUCUUAGAAAAGAGGUCGGGCCAGGCGCUGUGGCUCACUCCUGUAAUCCCAGCACUUUGGGAGGCCAAGGCGGGCGGAUCAUGAGGUCGAGAGAUUGAGACCAUCCUGGCUAACAUGGUGAAACCCCGUCUCUACUAAAAAUACAAAAAAAUUAGCCGGGCGUGGUGGCGGGCGCCUGUAGUCCCAGCUACUCAGGAGGCUGAGGCAGGAGAAUGGCGUGAACCCGGGAGGUGGAGCUUGCAGUGAGCCGAGAUCGCGCCACUGCACUCCAGCCUGGGCGACAGAGCGAAAAAAAAAAAAAAAGAAAAAGAAAAAGAAAAGAGGUCAAGGACUCCGUCCUUGGAAUCCUAAGAAAAUUUUCCAGCCGUAUUACCCUUCUAUGAAGCCCACCUGUCAACCAACAAGCACCCACUCGAUCAGAGCUUCCCCAGGCUUUUUGGUGUCUCCUCCUUGCAUGGGAAUUGACUUCCAAGGACCACCAGACACUGAGGAAGUAUUUUAACAUAUAAAGCAAAAGCAACAAUAGGGCAGCUGGAGAAAGGAAAUUAGAAGUAACAGAGCCAAUGCAGUGAUUAGAAAAACACUCAAAAAAUGGUAAUAAAUGUGUUCAAUGGGUCAAGAGAACAUAUUUCCAUCUAUUUAAAUAAAAACAGGAAUCAAUAAAAGUGAACAUACAAAAAAGAGCUCUUGUCACAGAAAUGAAAACCUUGGGAGCAGGACUGCACCCACGGUUCCCACCAACCUAUCCUGCCAUCAUGUUUUCUCCCUACUCCAGCUUCCUCCCAAGCUCACUCUACGUAGAUGGUUUUUCUUCCCUUAGCCAACAAACGAAAUUCUGCCUAUAAAUUAAGCCAGGACACUAGGAUAUGGAGGUAUAUUAUUUAUGUCUCUUUUCCAGUGUUUCCUGGUAUAUAACAGCAAAGAUGGUUUAGCAAGUUAACUGGUCAGGCCAGAAUUCUUGAUGGUUGCCAAGUCAGGAGGCAGACGGUGAAGGAAUGCAUUCUGGUUAUGAAAAAUGGCAAUGACGAGUAAGUUGCAGAGUAAAGAUGCCUUUUAGAGGAAAUUAAGGUUUGCAAUAAAUGCAUGCUAAUCCUCUAAUUUUGAUGAAAGACUAAAGCUCUUGUUUUGGUUUGCAUUUCAAAGAGCAAGAGCAUAGGCUCUUGUGCUGGGAGGUGGCCAGUUUCCUGGAAAGGAAUUUAUGGAGUCUGAAAGAGGAAUUAGUACAAAUUAUAUUUUCAAAUAAGAUACUUGAAAGUUAUUGAUGACAGGGAAAAGAUUGUCUAAAGAGGGCUUGAAAUUGGGGAAAUAAUUGAGGCUCAGUGACAAAGGAGAAGAUUACAACUUCAAAAAUGAAUAAAUAAAUAACAUUGCAUGUUUAUUUUACAA